AGUCACUGUGUCCUUCCUCUUGCUCUCUUCCUGACGUUAGCAGAGGACUGGGACUCGCGAGAGAGGACUCACGGACCUCCAGGACCUAUUAACUUGACAGACCCGCCCCUCUAUUCGAGCCAGCCCAACUCGGAGAACUCAGAGUCAUCCUCGAGAGUAAAGAAAGCUCUUAGAGUUUUUUUUUUUUGACAAAUCUAUCUUAAAUGUCAGUCCAAUAUCCACGGCGACGAGCCACAGCAGGUGAGAAACCUGGAAAUGAGCCUGAAGAGGUGAAGCUGCAGAAUGCCAGCAAACAGAUUGUGCAGAAUGCAAUCCUGCAAGCUGUGCAGCAAGUCUCCCAGGAGAGUCAGCGCAGAGAAGAGAGAAUCAGUGACAACCGGGACCACAUCCAACUGGGCGUUGGGGAGUUAACCAAGAAGCACGAAAAGAAGUAACAUGGUGGAUUUGGCUCUUGACAUGUGCUUGGUUUCUAGCCUUCCUCUUAGUAUAGGACGCAUCUCCAAAAUGUUGCCAGUAAAGCAAACCGAAGUGUCACCGGCACCUAGCUGUAGAAUGAAUUCACACUAGCCCCUGGCUGAGAAGCACUGUUUUGAAAAAGUGCAUUAGACGAUUCUGUUCAUAUUUAUGCAGUGCCUCUGAGACAUAGUGGGGCCAAAUAUGACACUGUAAUUGCAAAAGUAGUUUUGCAGGCCAAUUUAUUUUUAAAGUUCUUUUAUUUGAAAAAAAGAAUUCUAUGUCUCGUUUAUUUACUUCUGCCUUUUAUGCGUUCCUUCUGUGAAUUUAACAAGCAGCCUUUUUGCUGAAAUACUGAAUACAGUACUGAGUUCUUUAUGGUAUAUUAAAAAGACAUGCUAGAAAGGUGAGGGAAUGCAGUUUUAGUUACCUUCAAAUGUGAAAUUGAAGGCUUUAAGUGGGUUCAGGUCUAAGAUCAAAUUAAGAAAAGGGAAAUUCUAAGGCUGAGUCCCUCGGGACCAUACCAAGGCAUUUACUAAUAUUUAUGUUAUUUUAAGAAAGGGAGGAGUUUAAGUUUCUCAAGAACUCAGUCUUUUAGUCUCAAUUCUCUGAAUGAUUUCAUAAUUGGUGUUUAUGCUCUGUGUAGAAAUCUUUUGGGAAUAUUAUGGAUUUCUUUUCUCAAGAUUAAAUAAAAUAAGACAAGUGAGUCUACACAUGUGAGUUGCCAAUGACUCAUUUCCUUAGCAGCCUCAUGGAGAAUGGCUAGAAGUGUAGAUUUCUUCAACAGCUGCCUAUCAUUAAGAGACUUACACUUGGGGCUGAUUAUGGGGUGCAACAUCCUUGGAAGGGAUUCUGGGGUCCUUAACGAAUGCUGUUUUGCCACUAGGCUAUGCAUUUGCAUUAGGACCUUACUAACUUUUCCCAUUCACACAUUAAAUUUUUUUUUUGAGAUUAUGAAAAUCAUACAGGUCAGGAAUACAUGAGAACACAAUGGGGACAGUAAAGUGACAGUGUUUUGAAUGCAGUGACAGAGAUAUGUGUGUGUACACGUGUAAUAAAGUUAUCUGUGCAGCAACAGGAUCAAUCCCUGCUCCACUUCUGUGAGGAUAAUGCACAUAUUUCUGGAGUAUCUACAGUCCCAUUUCCUGGGCUUCACAAAAGUUAUUGAAUUGGUGCUAUUGGGGACAGAGGAAGAAUUUGACCUUGGUUAAAAACCUUCUAGUUUCAGAGUAUCAAUAUCUACAUUUGAUUUUUUUUUAAAGCAAAGUAUUCGGGUAUAAAUUGUGACUGAUAUUAAGAUAUACUUCUAAAAUUCCAAUAUGCUACAGUUUCUAGAAUAAAUAGUUGGAUAAUAGAUAAUGAAUGAAAAAUAUCUUACCAGCUUUGUUAUGCUAUCUCCCACAGUGCACAGGUGGAAUAAAUUCACAGGAAACAUGGAAGGAGAAGGAAGCAGAAGGGCUUAAAAUUUAAAGAUUGUUUACUCACAAGUAUUUCUUUUAGCAGAAUUCAUGCCAAGUGAAGAGUGAGUUUAAGUCGACCAAAAGUCAUAUAACUGAUGUGAUAUAAUUGCAUAGCAUACAUAGUGAGAAUGAAGGUAUUCAGGGAAAUUAUUCAGGAGUGCCACAAAUAAAAUAAAUAAAUAAAUCUAAUGCUUGUAGUUUGUAAGUGAUCUGGUACUAUGUCUACUCAGAUAUCUGGAUAUGACCAGCCUUUGUUUUUGCUGUCAAGUGACAGAAACAUAUAAACAUACUAUUUUUCCUCUCUGAUGUGUCUGUACUAAAAAAUUGGGAAUUUUUGGAACAUCUUAUUGACCUCUGUGUCUAAAUGUUAUUUAUAAAUAAAACACAUACAGCUUUGAAAUAUCUUAAGCAAAGUUUUCUAGACUCUGCCGUUUGGCUCAUUUUGUACGUGGAUCUUACCAUUAUUUGGAACCAUGAGACUUCCAAGGCUAUUUUCAAACCCCUAGAUAUCAUGACCAGGGGAAGUGCUUCCUUAAUGGGCCCUUCACUGUGACUGUGUGAGGACAGCCAUGGGAUGGUGGGUCCUGAGGCUUGAAGAGAAAAGGAUGUAUGCUAAGAAGUGGUCUUUUGAUCUAAAAAAUUCAAGGUAAGUGGGUCUGGAAGGUAGAGUGUCUGCCAUAAUUUUUGAGAUGGAAAAUCGACAGCAAGGAACAGAGAUAUGACUAAGUUGUUGGGAGGACAAAAGGAGGUUCAGCAAUGCCUGUCCUCAAUAGGUAGGUGCCAUAUUGGCAAAAUUCUAAGAAAGCUCAGUCAUAAAAACAAACGAGUUAAAGACCUAUAAACUUUUACAGAUCUUUCAGUAUGAAGAAAAAGUUACUAGAUUUUACAAGGGGCCUACAGAACUUCAUUUGACAUAGGAUUAAGGUGGAUUUCCACUUGAUUAUCAUCAUAAACCAGAUCACAGCUUUUAGUUUCAGAAAUGAGUGGGAACAUUUACUUAGUGUCCUUUAUCUUUCUGAUUUACUGCAUACACAGGCUUCCCAUCUCUGUGUGUUCAGCUGUUCGUCUUCUCUGUUGCCUGCCCCUAGGGUGGAUCUAAAGAAAGAAAUCCUUUCAUGUUACUUUUCUCUGCUGUAAUCAUCUGUUCAGUGCAAACAGUAUUGUAAAUUGAU